CUCUCCACCGACUGCAACCUCCGUGCUCACAGCUCACGGUUCACCAGAAUCCAGGGGCUUGGUCGGCCUAGGAAUCCACAAUGCUGGAUAUUUUCAUCCUGAUGUUCUUUGCCAUCAUAGGCCUGGUCAUUCUGUCCUACAUUAUCUAUCUGCUCUAGUGGCCUGGAGCUGCGGCCGGAGCCUGCUGGAGAACAGCUCAGAAGGAAGGAUGGAGAUGAAUGGCCGAGUGCCCUGCUUGCUGACGCACCGGUGGAUUUUUGCUUCUGCUGUUAUCUCGGCUCCUGGUCUCUCCAGUCCAACAAGAGGCCUCUCAUCCACAGAAGCAGUCCUACUGCCCAGCAGACCUCUUUCAGAGCCUUCCAGACAUGGCUGACCCCUGGCAAGCAAGGGGCUUUUUGAGCUGAGAGGCACUUGGCUGGGACUUCAGGAAUUCAUGGACAGGGCUGGCAGAUACUGCAUAUGUUUGAGCUGUAGAUGGGAUUGAGAACAGAAAGUUGAAAUGGAGACUUAUUAAAGUUACCGUGGAGAACUGCUCAAAAAUUCAUUUUGAAUUAAGGAAACUUAAAUUCAUUUUAAGUUUCCUUAGAUCUAAAUGCAACUGCACAUUACACUCAAAUAUGUUCCUUCCUUCUCACACACAGGACUCCCUUGUGAAACUCAAGGGGAAGUUCAAGUUGUCCAUCUUCAUCUAUGAAGUAGUCACUUUAUCACUGUCUUUACAGAUUGCACAGUCUGGGGUUUUGUGGUUUCUCUUGUCUCACUCUCCAGCCAGGAAGAACUUGUCAUUUGAGUUUUUAAAAUGUAUCAUUUCUUCCCCACCUCAAACCACUUGUAUCCCAGUUUCUCAUUUAAAGGGAGAAAUGGUUAUAUAGUCCUCUCUUUGCACCUGAUUGAAUUAUAAAUGAUAGAAACAAGAUGGCUAUACUUAUUUAGGAAAAAUCUCUUACCCCAAAAUGAGUGUGUGUGUGUGUGUGUGUGUGCGUGUGUGUGUGUGUGUGUGUUUUAAUCAAAGAUCUUUUCUGGAAAAAACUUUCCACAUAGUUCUCUGACCCAUUAGAGUUGAAGAAACUAUGUAUUUUGGGAUUCAGAGUAGAAUUGGCCUGCAAAUCUGGGGUGUUUAUUCCUUUUACAAGUCUAUCAUAAUUGUUCUACAUUUAAUUUUCCUUUCUUGCUUAAAAGUAAACAAGGAGAGUCAGGAGUGGUGGCUCAUGCCUGUAAUCCCAGCACUCUGGGAGGCCGAGGCGGAUGGAUCACCUGAGGUCAGGAGUUGGAGACCAGCCUGGCCAACACGGUGAAACCCCGUCUCUACUAAAAAUACAAAAAUUAGUCAGGCACAGUAGUGCGCGCCUGUAGUCCCAGCUACCCGGGAGGCUGAGGCCGAAGAAUUGCUUGAACCCGGGAGGCAGAGGUUGUAGUGAGCCGACAUCAUGUCACUGCACUCCAGCCUGGGAGACAUAGCGAGAUUCCGUCUCAAAUAAAAUAAAAUAAAUAAAUAAAUAAACAAGGAGAAAGAUUAGUUUUUAGUAAUAACAUUGUGUCCAAUUUCCAUGUUUUAAAACAAAAAUUGAGGCAUUAUAUGUCACAACUGAAAUGGAAAAGUUGUGUUUAAAAAUUAUGGACAAGGCCGGGCACGGUGGCUCACGCCUGGAAUCCCAGCACUUUGGGAGGCUCAGGCAGGAGGAUCACUUGAGGUCGGGAGUUUGAGACCAGUCUGACCAACGUGGUGAAACCCUGUCUCUACUAAAAAUACAAAAAUUAGCUGGUGUGGUGGCAGGUGCCUGUAAUCCCAGCUACUCAGGAGGCUGAGGCAGGAGAAUCGCUUGAACCUGGGAGGCAGAGGUUGCAGUGAGCCGAGAUCACACCUCUGCACUCCAGCCUAGGUGACACAGCAAGACCCCAUCUCAAAAAAAAAUAAUAAUAAAAACAUAAAAAUUAUGGACAAGAAAAAACACUAUUCUGGAAGCUUUGUUUUGGCAACAAAUUAUAUGACCUGACCUUUCAUAAGUCAUUUAAACUUUAGGGCUAGGCCAGGUGCUAUGGCGCAUGCCUAUAAUCCCAGCAUUUAGGGAAGUAGAAGCAGGAGGAUAGCUUGAGGCCAAGAAUUCCAGACCAGCCCAGGCAAUAUAGCGAGACCCCCGUCUCCACAAAAAUAAAAAAUAAAAUAAAAAUAAAUAAAUACAUAAACUUUAGGUCCUCUGUUUAUUCUGUCAAAUGAAAGUGUUAGGCCAAGGUCGCAUUAUCUCUUUGGAAACUACAUCGAGAACAGAAUUCCCAUGGAACGAACUCUUAAUAGUUCACUGGUAGUCCCCCUUUUCUGAAUAUUCUUCCCAACAUGACACUUUAUAACAAAAAUUUAACUGCAAAACUCUUUUUUUUUCACCAACAGCCAGAUUUUGAUGAGAAAAUGGCCAUAUUUAUUUACUCCAAAUAUAUAUUAUGUCUGUGAUAAUUUGCCUAAACUGUUUAAGGAAUAUUAACAAGUAUGAUACUGCAUCGUGGUAUGUAGCAAAAAGAUAGGUAAUCUGACAUACAUGGAUGCAAGCAGCAUGGCUGUGAACCUGGAUAUAUUUAGAAAUGAUCUUCAGUGGAGUCCUUGAUGUGACAUUUUCCACUAAAACAUUCUUCUAACUCUGGUAUAUCUUAGUGUUUCGAACUAUAAUUUCCGUCUUCAAGCCAAGACAGCAGCUCUACAUCCUUACCUAGGUAAUUCAGGCAUGCGCCAGUAUUUUGGAGGGGUCCAAAUUAGAGUUAGUUAUGAUGGUAUAGAUCUUUAAAGUAUAGUCUAACCAAGCUUGCUCUGGUCUUUUGUGACAUCAAGGCUUCUCAGUCUGUAUUCACAUAAAGUUGAAACAACUAAUCAAUUCAGUGAAAAAAAAUCAGCAGAUUUCACUCAUACACUGGUGAUAUAUACCACUGGUAUUGGGUACAAUGUAAGGAGAGAGGAUUACCCAUCUCUUCAGUUACUUGUAAAAUAUGAUUUUAAAAAAAUAAAUCAAUACAUUUUGGAAAAAUUAUAUGACUUUGUGCUUAUAUUUAUGCAACAAUAUGCUAGCUUAUAACAGGGUUUUACUGUGUUAUUUUGAUAGUUGUUUAAAUUUUACAUUUAAACUAUUUGUAUUUUGGCAUCCCAAAACAUAAUAAAACACUGCAAAAAGUUACCUCUGUAAUAUAAGAUUUUGUAUAAAUUUUAUAAAUUUGUGUCAUAGGGUAAUUUUGUCCAAUAAAAUGUCAAUGAGAUAAAAA